CUUUCCGCCCGGCUCCUUCAGAGGCCCGGCGACCUCCAGGGCUGGGAAGUCAACCGAGGUUCGGGGGCAGCGGCGAGGGCUCCGGGCGAGUAAGGGGGAUGGUCCAUGCUGAGGCCCAAAUGGGGCGAACUCGCGAGAGUCUCUGGCGACCUGGAUCAGAUGGGGCGAGGGCAGAUGAAGGGCCCAGGAGCUUUGGGGCAGCGAGGAGGGAGGAGCGGGCCCGUUGGCAAACUUGGGUGAAAGGAUGGGGUACCUGGGUGACGAGCCCCCGCCAGGAUUCUGCUCUUCACGCCCCUUUUCUCCCAGCUCCCUUCCAGGUCAAUCCAAACUGGAGCUCAACUUUCAGAAGAGAAAGACGCCCCAGCAAGCCUCUUUCGGGGAGUCCUCUAGCUCCUCACCUCCAUGGGCCAGACAGCUCUGGCAGGGGGCAGCAGCAGCACCCCCACGCCACAGGCCCUGUACCCUGACCUCUCCUGUCCCGAGGGCUUGGAAGAGCUGCUGUCUGCACCCCCUCCUGACCUGGGGGCCCAGCGGCGCCACGGUUGGAACCCCAAAGACUGUUCAGAGAACAUCGAGGUCAAGGAAGGAGGGUUGUACUUUGAGCGGCGGCCCGUGGCCCAGAGCACUGAUGGGGCCCGGGGUAAGAGGGGCUAUUCAAGGGGCCUGCACGCCUGGGAGAUCAGCUGGCCCCUAGAGCAGAGGGGCACGCAUGCCGUGGUGGGCGUGGCCACGGCCCUCGCCCCGCUGCAGACUGACCACUACGCGGCGCUGCUGGGCAGCAACAGCGAGUCGUGGGGCUGGGACAUCGGGCGGGGGAAGCUGUACCAUCAGAGCAAGGGGCCCGGAGCCCCCCAGUAUCCAGCGGGAACUCAGGGUGAGCAGCUGGAGGUGCCAGAGAGACUGCUGGUGGUUCUGGACAUGGAGGAGGGAACUCUGGGCUACGCUAUUGGGGGCACCUACCUGGGGCCAGCAUUCCGCGGACUGAAGGGCAGGACCCUCUAUCCGGCAGUAAGCGCUGUCUGGGGCCAGUGCCAGGUCCGCAUCCGCUACCUGGGCGAAAGGAGAGCGGAGCCACACUCCCUUCUGCACCUGAGCCGCCUGUGUGUGCGCCACAACCUGGGGGAUACCCGGCUCGGCCAGGUGUCUGCCCUGCCCUUGCCCCCUGCCAUGAAGCGCUACCUGCUCUACCAGUGAGCCCUGUGAUACCACAGACUGUGCUGAGGUCUUGCCACCACCCCUCCCCUUGGGGAGGUGGGGAGGCACUGCUGGCCUAGACCAGCUGCUGAAAGCUGGUGAGGCUGAGCCCCUACCCCAACCCAAGCUCUGCGGAAAUCAACAGCCCCAGAGCCACUUGGAGGGAGGAAGAAAGGGAGCCGGCGUUCAAGGCUAUGACAGUCUGCUACGCAAAACAUUUUUUCAAGUAAAAAUAGUAAGAGAUGUUGUUAUAGAAA